CUCCUCCCCGCCGCCGCCCUCGCCAUGGCCGCGCCGGCCCCGGGCCUCAUCUCGGUGUUCUCGAGUUCCCAGGAGCUGGGUGCGGCGCUAGCGCAGCUGGUGGCCCAGCGCGCAGCAUGCUGCCUGGCAGGGGCCCGCGCCCGUUUCGCGCUCGGCCUGUCGGGCGGGAGCCUCGUCUCGAUGCUAGCCCGCGAGCUACCCGCCGCCGUCGCCCCUGCCGGGCCAGCUAGCUUAGCGCGCUGGACGCUGGGCUUCUGCGACGAGCGCCUCGUGCCCUUCGAUCACGCCGAGAGCACGUACGGCCUCUACCGGACGCAUCUUCUCUCCAGACUGCCGAUCCCAGAAAGCCAGGUGAUCACCAUUAACCCCGAGCUGCCUGUGGAGGAGGCGGCUGAGGACUACGCCAAGAAGCUGAGACAGGCAUUCCAAGGGGACUCCAUCCCGGUUUUCGACCUGCUGAUCCUGGGGGUGGGCCCCGAUGGUCACACCUGCUCACUCUUCCCAGACCACCCCCUCCUACAGGAGCGGGAGAAGAUUGUGGCUCCCAUCAGUGACUCCCCGAAGCCACCGCCACAGCGUGUGACCCUCACACUACCUGUCCUGAAUGCAGCACGAACUGUCAUCUUUGUGGCAACUGGAGAAGGCAAGGCAGCUGUUCUGAAGCGCAUUUUGGAGGACCAGGAGGAAAACCCGCUGCCCGCCGCCCUGGUCCAGCCCCACACCGGGAAACUGUGCUGGUUCUUGGACGAGGCGGCCGCCCGCCUCCUGACCGUGCCCUUCGAGAAGCAUUCCACUUUGUAGCUGGCCAGAGGGACGCCGCAGCUGGGACCAGGCACGCGGCCCAUGGGGCUGGGCCCCUGCUGGCCGCCACUCUCCGGGCUCUCCUUUCAAAAAGCCACGUCGUGCUGCUGCUGGAAGCCAACAGCCUCCGGCCAGCAGCCCUACCCGGGGCUCAACACACAGGCUGUGGCUCUGGACAUCCGGAUAUUAAAAGGAGCGUUGCUGGAA